CGGUAGGUCGCCAGCUGAGGCGGUUUGUAAGUUUUGGGUCGCAGUAUGCUAGAAUUUUGAGGCUCCCUUCUGAUGAAAAUUGAGCUGUCCAUGCAGCCAUGGAACCCGGGUUACAGCAGUGAGGGGGCCACGGCUCAAGGCCGGGCGCAGUGGCUCACACCUGUAAUCCCAGCACUUUGGGAGGCCGAGGCGGGCGGAUCAUGAGGUCAGGAGAUCAAGACCAUCCUGGCUAACACGAAACUUACACAUGUCCAAAAAUGAUUGAGAUGGAGCAGGCGGAGGCCCAGCUUGCUGAGUUAGACCUGCUAGCCAGUAUGUUCCCUGGUGAGAAUGAGCUCAUAGUGAAUGACCAGCUGGCUGUAGCAGAACUGAAAGAUUGUAUUGAAAAGAAGACAAUGGAGGGGCGAUCUUCAAAAGUCUACUUUACUAUCAAUAUGAACCUGGAUGUAUCUGACGAAAAAAUGGCGAUGUUUUCUCUGGCCUGUAUUCUUCCCUUUAAAUACCCGGCAGUUCUGCCUGAAAUUACUGUCAGAUCAGUAUUAUUGAGUAGAUCCCAGCAGACUCAGCUGAACACAGAUCUGACUGCAUUCCUGCAAAAACAUUGUCAUGGAGAUGUUUGUAUACUGAAUGCCACAGAGUGGGUUAGAGAACACGCCUCUGGCUAUGUCAGCAGAGAUACUUCAUCUUCACCCACCACAGGAAGCACAGUCCAGUCAGUUGACCUCAUCUUCACGAGACUCUGGAUCUACAGCCAUCAUAUCUAUAACAAAUGCAAAAGAAAGAAUAUUCUAGAGUGGGCAAAGGAGCUUUCCCUGUCUGGGUUUAGCAUGCCUGGAAAACCUGGUGUUGUUUGUGUGGAAGGCCCACAAAGUGCCUGUGAAGAAUUCUGGUCAAGACUCAGAAAAUUAAACUGGAAGAGAAUUUUAAUUCGCCAUCGAGAAGACAUUCCUUUUGAUGGUACAAAUGAUGAAACGGAAAGACAAAGGAAAUUUUCCAUUUUUGAAGAAAAAGUGUUCAGUGUUAAUGGAGCCAGGGGAAACCACAUGGACUUUGGUCAGCUCUAUCAGUUCUUAAACACCAAAGGAUGUGGGGAUGUUUUCCAGAUGUUCUUUGGUGUAGAAGGACAAUGACAUCAAGAGUAGUUGAAAGUAUCUUGCCACUGUUGGCCUUUUGAUUUUUUUUUCCCACUUUUUCUUGAAAGAUUAAGUAAUUUUAUUUUAGUUCCAUUCUAGAAUGUUGGGGAGUGGGGCACAAGAAAAAAUAGUAUAGCUGAAAUGCAUCUGUUAAAAAUGUCAUGAUUGAAAGCAGAACUGAGUUUCAAAUUACAACCUUAAAAUUGUUGUUAGAUAUUUCUUCACAUAUCAGCUGCCCAUUUUGAAAAAGAAAUUAUCCAUAAAGGUAAUGUUGGUGCUCCAAUUUGCCAGCCAUUCCCAACCCCCUUCUCCCUUACCUGCCUUCACUAAAGAACCCAGAAAAGCUAAUUGCUCCCCUUUCAGCCUCUGUUGCAACUAACAACUCUCAGUGGCCUCAGGACACAGCUUUGGCCUUGGGAAUUCUGGGAAAACUUUUACUUCCUGAUUAAAGAUACAUAUGCAGCUAGGCCACCUCCUCCCCCCCUUACUGCCAUAAACACCAAAGUGAUGACUGGAGCUGGAGGAGUUAUUUGAACCACGACGAAGGGCCAAGAGAACCACGAAGAUGCCAGUUGCCACAUUGUUGAGCUGCUGACCCAACACCAGCCAUUGCCUGUCUCUAAACAUCUUAUGAAAUAAAACCAGUUUUGUUUAAUUUCUAGGCUUUUUUUUUAAAUAGACGGAGUCUUGCUCUGUCGCCCGGGCUAGAGUGCAAUGGUGCAACCUCCGCUCACUGCAACCUCCGCCUCCCAAGUUCAAGCGAUUCUCCUGCCUCAGCCUCCCAAGUAGCUGAGAUUACAGGCGCCCGCCACCAUGCCUGGCUAAUUUUUGUGUUUUUUAGUAGAGACAGGGUGUCACCAUUUUGGCCAGGCUGGUCUUGAACUCCUGACCUCAGGUGAUCCUCCCACCUCGGCUUCCCAAUGUGCUUGGAUUACAGGCAUAAGCCACCGUGCCUGGCCAAUAUCUAGGCUUUUUACUAGCAGUUGAAAGCUAGUUUGUCAAAUAGAGUUUUUCAGAGCUUUAGUUUUGCAUUUACCCCAGCCUUUUGAUACACAAAUAGGUGAAGUUUUUCUGAAGUGGAGUUUGCAGUUCCCCACUUUUUGUAUACUCACGCUCUGCCCCUGCUCCUGGGCUUGCCUCAGACAAGGCUGAGGCAUUAGUAGGGCUUAAACUUUUUUAACAAGCCUCAACAAUUCAUCAAAUUAGUAAUUUAGAAAAUUUGUUUGGCAAAUUGUAUUCUGACAUUUUUUGUUCUGGAAAUGGCUUUCUGUACAUUUAUUUUUGCCAAAUUGACCUAGCAUUAAAUAAACACACCACCCAGUUUUUGAGGACCUCCAUAAACCAGUUAGUUCCAAAAGCAUUUAUUAUUUGCUAAUUUGCUAGCAUGCAGGUUGAUGCAGGUUGAUACCAGGUGUUGGAUAUUUCUUGACCAGUCAGACUUGGUUAAGGAAUGGAGUUGGGGUGAGAGACAAUGCAUUAAGUUAGUAAAAGGUUGUAGGCAAACUAUGCUUAUCACAAAAUGAAUCAGUUAGUAAAAGACAGCAUAUAUUAUGUAAUACAAUGUAGAAAUCUGAAGGAAUAAAAUGGAAGAAGGCAAUGUGGAUAGAUCUUAAAUAUAAAGGUGGUUAAACAUAAAUGAGAAUCAGAAUGGUAUUUAAAGCACAGUGCUUGUAUUGGACCUAAAUCUUAUGUACGUCCCCAGAUUUCCUCCCUGCUGCCCUGUCCUAUCGCCCCGUCAGUUGCCCUGGAAAUCCCAGUUCCUCUGCUGCCACCAGACAGCCAGGUGGACCAGUUGUGUGUCUAGUUUCUGAUUCCUCCAGCGACUAACAGAUUUGUAUGAAAUACCCUACAGAGAAUGGAAUCUGACAUCCCUACCACCAAAGGGGGCAGAUGAUGCAUAUAUUACUUUAAGCAGCUAAAGUGGCAGCUAAACUGCUAAAACUUUUUCAGUCUCUCUACAUUAUAUUAAAAACCAGAUUGCUAUGUAUAAUAUGCAGAUCUCAAAUGUCACAUAAACACAUAGAAUGCAA